AGUCUAGGUGCAGCUGCCGGAUCCUUCAGCGUCUGCAUCUCGGCGUCGCCCCGCGUACCGUCGCCCGGCUCUCCGCCGCUCUCCCGGGGUUUCGGGGCACUUGGGUCCCACAGUCUGGUCCUGCUUCACCUUCCCCUGACCUGAGUAGUCGCCAUGGCACAGGUUCUCAGAGGCACUGUGACUGACUUCCCUGGAUUUGAUGAGCGGGCUGAUGCAGAAACUCUUCGGAAGGCUAUGAAAGGCUUGGGCACAGAUGAGGAGAGCAUCCUGACUCUGUUGACAUCCCGAAGUAAUGCUCAGCGCCAGGAAAUCUCUGCAGCUUUUAAGACUCUGUUUGGCAGGGAUCUUCUGGAUGACCUGAAAUCAGAACUAACUGGAAAAUUUGAAAAAUUAAUUGUGGCUCUGAUGAAACCCUCUCGGCUUUAUGAUGCUUAUGAACUGAAACAUGCCUUGAAGGGAGCUGGAACAAAUGAAAAAGUACUGACAGAAAUUAUUGCUUCAAGGACACCUGAAGAACUGAGAGCCAUCAAACAAGUUUAUGAAGAAGGCAGUAAGUUCCCAACCGCUAAGGCAGAAGUGAUACAUGUAUCUCAACUUUGAACUUUAUUUGAUGUACUAUUCAAAGAUCUCUUUCUGGGGAUGUUGACGUUGAUGAGAGCCUUUGUGCUACUGGAUUACAAAUGGUGUGCUCAAAGGGGGUAAUAACUGUGUGGUCUGUCCUACUCAGCCGUGUAAUUGAGCACUGGCUAUGUGUCUGGCAGUGUGUUAACAGGCUGUCAUGAGUGACAAAAGGUGUGCAUAACACAGCUCCUGUCCUCAAGCAGUUUGUGUGCAGUCUCCUCAGUGGGUGACAUGACAGAAUGACUGCAAUAUUUAAAGGAUAAUGAAAUUCAAACUAAAGUAAAAUACCAAUGAUGUUAAAUGCAAUAAUGCAUUCAGAAGAGAGAGGUCAUCAUAGCUUUGGAUGUUAGGGAGGCUUCAUGGUACAAAUCACACAUGCAGCAGAGUUUCAAGACUAGGUGGGUUUACAAAGUGUCCAUUGACAGAUGAAUAGAUAAAGAAUACGUACACACACACACACAAACACAGACACACACACACAGGAGUACUGUUCAGUCUUAAAGAGGGGAAAUCCUGUCAUUUCAACAUCAUGGAUAAACGUGGAGGACAUAAUGCAAAGUGAAAUAAGCUAGGCACAAGGCAUAAGCUAUGCAUGAUCUCACUUCUUAUGUUGAAUCUAAAAAAAUUGAACUCAUAGAAACAGAUAGUAAAACAGUGUUUGCUAGGGUGUAGGGGUGGGGUGAAUGGGAGAAGGGACUGGUGAAAUAUUGGUCAAAGCAUACACGAUUUUAGUUAGGCAGGAUGAAUAAGUUCUGGGGAUCUCAUGAACAGCGUGGUGACUAUAGUGAAAGUAUAACUAUUAUAUGCUUGAAAUUUGUGAAUACAGUAUAUUUUAAAUGUCCUCACCACACACAAAAAUAUAGACUAUAUGAAGUGAUGGAUAUGCUGAUUAACUUGAUUGUGGUAAUCAUUUCACAACGUACACAUAUAUGAAAACAUCAUGGUGUAUACCUUAAAUAUAUACAAUUUUUAUUUGUCCAUCAUAACUCAAUAAAGCUGGGAAAAAAAGACUAGGUGCAUUUUGAGUAGGUAGAAAAGAUAUUUUUGGGUGAGGUACUGCCUGUCUUUAAUGGCAUGGAGACUGGACUGUGGAGAGUGUAUUGAGGGACGGAGAGGGCCUGGCUGCUGUGGAGGAUGUGUGCAUGUCCAUUGUGGGAGGUAAAUGGAACAAGCGAGGUUAGGCUCAGAUAUAGAUGGUUUUGCAUGACUGGAUUAGGAAUUUGGACUUAAUUCACAGGCACUGUAAAUUCCUGAAUGAGCAGUGGAGUGCUGAAGGAACAAUUGAGGGAGGAAGGAGAUUUGAAUUGAGAGGCUAAUUGGAUAGUUAUGUGUGUGGGAGGUAAGCUAGGUAUUUAGGAAUUGUGGCCCAACCUAGGUGAGUGAGAGGUGUGAGGAGGAUAAAUCAGGGACAGGAGAAACGUGAUAGGAUUUAAUGGUUAAUAUUUACAGGUGUUGGUGUAGAAGAAAGAAUUAAAGAUUCCUACAAGGUUUUGUAUUUGGGUAACUUGUUGAAAUAAACAUGUAACUCUUCUGGGCCUUUUAAAAUAGAAGUUUCAGGCUUUUAAAGUUCGUUUGCUUUUGCAUAAUAAUUAAAUAUUUAAAUACCUUAGAGUAAGGCCUCCUUUCCUUUAAUAGCAUCUGUUUGAGAGUAGUGAGAAAGACUUGUAGACUCUUGUAGAUCCCAGUUCUCCCCUUUUAUAUGGGCUUACAUUGAGCAGCUGGAAAUAGAGGUGGGAGGGGGGCCUACUUUAAAAUAUCAUUGCUGUCUCUCAAGAGUUAACUUUAUUUCUGCAGAGGAAAAAUACCUUAUUAGGAGUGAUGGCCAUGCCCAAAGAAAUAAAUCUCAGAAUAUUAGAGAUAGAAGACAUUUGGAAGCUAACCAUAUAAAAGAUUUGAAAGAAAGCAAAACAGAGUUUAAGCUUAUGAUUGAUUGUGUUUUGGAGACUUUCCAGUACCAUCAUGUAUCUAUAGAUUAAUGACUACAUUGGUCGAGAGAAUUUCUAAAUGGCUGAGUCUUGAUUUAAGUUUGAAUUGAGUGCCUUUGGGAGACUUUAAUUCAUUUUUGUCCAACCACUCACUGAAAGCAUUUGCUUAGAGCAUUCAGAGAUGGAAUAGAGGGAAUUUAUGUUAACCAAAUAUAAUUAUUUCUUCUUUUACAUCGCUUUCAUUUGAUUAAUGGGGCAAGAUUACUUUUCUAGUUGAAAGAAGAUGUAAAUAAGUAUGAAAUUAUUUUGUUGCAGAAUAUGGCUCAAGCCUGGAAGAUGACGUGGUGGGGGACACUUCAGGGUACUACCAGCGGAUGUUGGUGGUUCUCCUUCAG